GAGGGCUGCGCCCACCUCCUUCCUGCCUCGGCAACCCCGGGCCCUGAGGGCAGGCCCCAACCGCGGAGGAGCAGGAGAGGGCGGAGGCCGGCGGGCCAUGCCCUGGUCGUCCCGCGGCGCCCUCCUUCGGGACCUGGUCCUGGGCGUGCUGGGCACCGCCGCCUUCCUGCUCGACCUGGGCACCGACCUGUGGGCCGCCGUCCAGUAUGCGCUCGGCGGCCGCUACCUGUGGGCGGCGCUGGUGCUGGCGCUGCUGGGCCUGGCCUCCGUGGCGCUGCAGCUCUUCAGCUGGCUCUGGCUGCGCGCUGACCCUGCCGGCCUGCACGGGUCGCAGCCCCCGCGCCGCUGCCUGGCGCUGCUGCAUCUCCUGCAGCUGGGUUACCUGUACAGGUGCGUGCAGGAGCUGCGGCAGGGGCUGCUGGUGUGGCAGCAGGAGGAGCCCUCUGAGUUUGACUUGGCCUACGCCGACUUCCUCGCCCUGGACAUCAGCAUGCUGCGGCUCUUCGAGACCUUCUUGGAGACGGCACCACAGCUCACGCUGGUGCUGGCCAUCAUGCUGCAGAGUGGCCGGGCUGAGUACUACCAGUGUACUGGGCUGCUGGGGGAUCCCAAGUGAGCAGAGUCUGUUUUCUACCCUCGAGGAGCCCAGAGAUAAGGAAAUAGAUAAUUACUGUGUGAUGAGACUCCAGACAGAGGCUAGGAGUGGGUUCUGGGCGCCUAAUAGGUUCCCAGUAAACAUCUGUCGAAUGACUGCGGUGGACGGGGACAGGGGAGGAAGCAGUCGGGAGACGUGCCGGUGCCACUUCCAUCCCUCCCUGGAGGCCCUUGUGCUUCUGCUCCAGGAUUGGCAACCAGGAGGGGUUGGCAUCUGCACAUCCUUCCUGGGCAUCUCGUGGGCACUGCUCGACUACCACCGGGCCUUGCGCACCUGCCUCCCCUCCAAGCCGCUCCUGGGCCUGGGCUCCUCCGUGAUCUACUUCCUGUGGAACCUGCUGCUGCUGUGGCCCCGAGUCCUGGCUGUGGCCCUGUUCUCAGCCCUCUUCCCCAGCUAUGUGGCCCUGCACUUCCUGGGCCUGUGGCUGGUACUGCUGCUCUGGGUCUGGCUUCAGGGCACAGACUUCAUGCCGGACCCCAGCUCCGAGUGGCUGUACCGGGUGACGGUGGCCACCAUCCUCUAUUUCUCCUGGUUCAACGUGGCUGAGGGCCGCACCCGAGGCCGGGCCAUCAUCCACUUCGCCUUCCUCCUGAGUGACAGCAUUCUCCUGGUGGCCACCUGGGUGACUCAUAGCUCCUGGCUGCCCAGCGGGAUUCCACUGCAGCUGUGGCUGCCUGUGGGAUGCGGCUGCUUCUUUCUGGGCCUGGCUCUGCGGCUUGUGUACUACCACUGGCUGCACCCUAGCUGCUGCUGGAAGCCCGACCCUGACCAGGUAGACGGGGCCCGGAGUCUGCUUUCUCCAGAGGGGUAUCAGCUGCCUCAGAACAGGCGCAUGACCCAUUUAGCACAGAAGUUUUUCCCCAAGGCUAAGGAUGAGGCUGCUUCGCCAGUGAAGGGAUAGGUGAACGGCGUCCUUUGAAGCAGGAUCAGACCCAGCCAGCAGAGAUGGAGAGUGACUCUGUUGGCAGAAGGCAGGCGAGGAUAAGCUAACGAUGCUGCUGUGGCCUCUAUGCACUCAGCAAGAGCGGGACGCCUGUGCUGGGCCGGGCACCAGGGAUGGUGCUGAGUCGGGCAGAGGCCUCCUUUCAAGGAGUUCACAGUGAACAAGAUGAGAAGGGCUGGGCCCUGGAGGGUCAAGAGCCCCAAUUAUGUACAAGACACUUUGGGAGGAAAGAAGACUACCUUUUCCCCCUGCCAUUGGUAUAGCUGGUGCCCCAAAACUUCCACCUCCCUCCCUGGCUACCUCUAAAAUGACUGGUAUAGGUGCUGCCCCACCCCUUAGCUCCCCUAUCCUGGGCUAGGAGGCCACAGGGGCUGUCCUCUAGAAUUCUUCCUUCCCUCCCCCACACCAUUCAUUCAAUUCAUGAAACAAAUCUUUGCCAAGAGCAGUUUAUGUGCCAGGAACAUCAUUCUGUCCUUGCAACCUGGAACAAGACCAGCUACCAGCCUAGCUUCAUCCGCUACUUGCACCAACCAGUCCCGGGUUAGAUCCCAAAUGCUAGAAGCCAGGGAUGCCCAACUCUGGGUGGCCCCAGUCAGAACCUCUGGGAUCUCAGUGAAGCUGGCCUGGCCUCUGCUCCUGCUCUCAAGGGGCUGCUUUUCAACCAAGAGCCUUGUGAGCCUGGUCUGAGCCUUGCACAGCCACUGAGUAUUUUUUUUGCCUUAGCCAGUGUACCUCCUACCUCAGUCUAUGUGAGAGGAAGAGAAUGUGUGUGCCUGUGGGUCUCUACAAGUGACAGAUGUGUUGUUUUCAACAGUAUUAUUAGGUUAUGAAUAAAGCCUCAUGAAAUCCUC